UCUUAAUUUAGGUCUUUAUGUGUGGAUAUCUAUUACCAUAUACGUGGUUUUUGCAUUACCAUUUGUUGAGAAAACUGUCCAUUUCCCAUUAAAUGGUCUUGGCACCUUUGUUGAAAAUUAUUCGACCACAAGUUUGAGGGUUUAUUUCUGGGCUGUGUAUUCUAUUCCAUUGGUCCAUAAGUUUGUUUUUAUGCCAAUACCACUCUAUUUUAAUUACUGUAGUUUUAUAGUAACUUUUGAAAUCAAGAAGUGUGAGACUCCACUUUGUUCUUUUCAAGAUUGUUUUGGUAGUUUGGGAUUCCUUGAGAUGCCAUAUGAAUUUUAGGAUGGGUUUUUCUAUUUCUGCAAAAAAUAGGCUAUUAGUAUUUUGUUAGGAAUUGUAUUGAAUCUCUAGGUUGCUUUGGGUAAUGUUGACAUCUAAAUACUGUCUUCCAGUCCAUGAACAUGGAAUAUCUUUCCAUUUAUUUGUGUCUUUAUUUCAGCAGUGUUUUUUAGUUUUCAGUGUAAAAGUCUUUUGUCUCCUUGUCUAAGUUUAUUCCUAAGUAUUUUAUUCUUUUUGAUGUGAUUGUAGAUAGGAUUCUUGUCUUAAUUUCUCUUUUGGAUUGUUCAUUGUUAAUGUUUAAGAAUGCAACUCAUUUUUGUGUGUUAAUUUUGUAUCCUACAACUUUACUGAUUUAUUAGUUCUAAUAGUUUUUUUGUGUGUGGAAUCUUUUUUGUGGAGUUUUCUACAUAUAGGAUCGUGUCAUUUGCAAACAGUUAAUUUACUUCUUGCUUUCGAAUUUGGAUGCCUUUUAUUUUUUUCCUUGCCUAAUCUCAGCUAGGACUUCCGGUACUGUGUCGACUAGAGGUGGUAAAAGCAGGCAUCCUUGGCUUGUUCCUGAUCUUAGAGGAAACGUUUUGAGUCUUUCCCUGUUGAAUAUGAUACUAACAUGAGUUUUUUAUAUAAGACCUUGAUUAUGUUCAGGUAGUUUCCUUAUAUUCCUGGUUUGUUGAGUGUUUUAACAGGUGUAUUUUAAGAAAAAUCAUUUGUGGGUGCUGAAAAGAAAGAAUUUCUAGCCUGGUGAGUGAGAGAAUCCUGGAGUCAUUGACAGAAUAAUAUAUUAUCAUGAAGUUGAUGUUUUAGGCAUCAUCUUUGUACAUUUACAGACCUGUUUUGAUUGAUAAAAAUAAUACUAUAGUUAUUUAGUGGGGAAGACUGACAUUACUCAAAUAAUUAUGCAGAUGUAUGUCUGAAUAACUAUAGUACAACUGGCUCACAUUUGUAUUUCUAGUAUCUAGCACUGUGCCUGGCACAGGGGCAUUCAGUGAAGUUGCUAAUUGAAUCAAGAAGCAGAAGAGUAAGGUUUAACCCAGUAAAGUAAAAAACAUAUUAUUAUAUAAUUUUUUAAUGGAAAUAAUGUUUAUUUUUAUUUUACCAGUUUUUAAUUUUCUUGAGACAGAGUCUCACUUUGACAGCGGGCUGAGCGCAGUGGUGUAGUCAUGACUCACUGCUGCCUUGGCCUCCUGGGCUCCAGCAAGCCUCCUGCCUCAGCCUCCCGAGUAGCUGGGAAUACAGGCACGUGCCACCAUGCCUGGCUAAUUUUUGUUGUGAGAGACAGGGCCUUGCAGUGUUGCCUAGGCUUUAUUUAAAACCAUUUUCCCUGUUAACCCAGUCUUGGUACAAUGGUAAUAAAGCAAAAUCAAAGUUCACCACUCUAGAAGAAUUAGGCAAGUGACUUUUUCUAAAACAGGUAUAGUAUCAUUAUUAAAGUGAGGUAACAGUUUUUCUUUUGACUUUUUUUUUUUUUUAGACAGAGUUUUGCUCUGUCGCCCAGGCUGGAGCGCAAUGGCGUGAUCCUGGCUCACUGCAACUGCUGCCUCCCAGGUUCAAGUGAUUCUCUCCUGCCUCAGCCUCCCAAGUAGCUGGGACUGUAGGUACGCGCCACCACACCUGGCUGAUUUUUGUAUUUUUAGUAGAGACAGGGUUUCGCCCCAUUGGCCAGGCUGGUCUCAAACUCCUUACAUAAGGUGACCCACCCGCCUCAGCCUCCCAAAUUGCUGGGAUUAUAGGCGUGAGCUACCAUGUCUGGCCCAGUUUUCUUUUUGGGUGAAUGCUAGUGGAAGUUAGUUAUCAGAAUCCAAAGUUUCAGAAGGAGGCUUUUUGCUCUGUCGCCUAAGCUGCAGUGGUGCAAUCACGACUCACCAGAACCUCAACUACCUGGGCUCAAGCAGUCUUUCCACCUCAGCCUCCUGAGCACCUGGGACUAUGGGCAUGUGCCACUAUGCCUGGCUAACUUUUGUACUUUUUCUGGAGAUGGGGUUUCACUGUGCUGCCCAGGCUGGUCUCGAACUCCAAGACUCCAGCAGUCCUCCAACCUUGGCCUCCCAAAGUGCUGGGAUUAUAGGUGUGAGCCACCAUGCCCAGCUGAGGCAUAAUUUCAACGAAACUUUUCAAGUGUCUGCUGAUUCCAGAUUUAUAAUGAAAUUUGAACAUUCAGCACUUAUUUGCAGAACAAGUUCAAAAGUUAAGAACCACCACGCUGUGGUGGUUUUUUGUUUUUGUUUUUUUAAUUUUAAAAUUUUGGACAGUUUGUAAAUUUGACAUCACAAAUUGAAUCUUUCAGAUACCCUUACUAUUUCAAAUAAUAUAGUAACUUUAGAAACAUAAUAUACUUAGUAUUAUAAAUUGACAUUAAAUCCAUGUCAUUGUGUGACAUGUGAGCAUUAUGUUAAGAUUGAAAUAGAUGGGGACACUUGGAAUAGCUAGGAAACACUUUAAUCCAAUACACAGAACAUUCUUUAAGUUACAGGAUUCAAAAUAGUUCCCUUUUAGAGCAUCGUUGGGGUUUUUAGAUAUAGUUGUGAUAGAACACCAGACUGGGAAUCAAACCUCCAUUUAGAUUCUGACUGAUGUUUAUAGUUUUAUGAUCUUAAAGCAAGUCACUUAACCUAUCUGAAGAUUAAUUUUCUCAUCUGUUAAAAUAGGUAUGGAAAUCUUGAAGCUUUUCUACCUUGUAUGUAUUUUUUUACUCCAUUGUUCCCCUCUCUAUUGCCACUCCCUUAUUAGUCUGGACUACGUAUUAAACAGCCUGCCAGCUAAGUCUCUGCAACUUGUUCUCCCACUGUACCUCUCCAUCUCUGGCUAUUCUCUAUAUUACUAUGACAAUUAUGUUCUUAAAAAACAGGCCAGACACGAUGGCUCACACCUGUAAUCCCAGCACUUUGGGAGGCUGAGGUGGGCGGAUCACCUGAGGUCGGCAGAUCACCUGAGGUCAGGAGUUCAAGACCAGUCUGGCCAACAUGGCGAAACCCCAUCUCUACUAAAGAUACAAAAAUCUGGUGUGGUGGCAGGUGCCUAUAAUCCCAGCUACUUGGGAGGCUGAGGCGGGAGAAUCGCUUGUCCCCAAGAGGCGGAGGUUGCAGUGAGCCAAGAUUGCGCCACUGCACUUCAGCCUGGGUGAUAGAGCUAGACUCUGUCUCAAAAAAAAAAAAAAAAAAAAAAAAAUUGGAGCAUGCUGCUUCUCUACUUAAAAUACCUUUGUUAACUUCCCUUGUCGAUAAAGUCCAGACUCACAAGAGUUUAUAGAAUGUGUUCAACCUUAGGUCUCCUGUCACUCCAGCCAUGCUGUUUCUUGUUCCCUGUGCCUCUGUCUUGUGUGUGUUUAUCCCAUUGUUUGGAGUUCUUAUUCUUUGCCUAUUCUGUUAGCUGCCCAUCUAAUGUCUACUUUUCUCUUCUUUCCUAACAGAAAUCUGCUUUUGUUCAUGCAUGCAGCAGACUUGGAGAAGCUGAUUUGUCACCACCUCCAGUAGUAGAGUUCCAUUAGUUCAAACCAGUCAAAUCAUGGCAUUUCCCUGUAAACUCUUAUUUGUACCGAUCAGAUUUGAAGGGAAGUAGACAUUCUGUUUCUGGGGGAGAAGAUUCUUUCCUCUCUUGUAUGUGAACAAGGGAACACAAGGCCCCUAUUGCUACCGACAGCUGUCUUGGGAUCACAAGGGAUGAAGCACUUCCUGAAGAUGGCAGAUCAGAGAGGUAGAGGGUAUCUGGAUCCUUGGUAACAUCAUUUAACCACAUAUUUUAUUGGGCCUGGAGCCAUCCCCACCACAGGACUUCUCAUGACAGAUAAUUUUCUUAAUGUUUCAGACAGUUCUUUGGAGUUAUUUGCCAUCAAAAAUCUCUUUUUUUUUUUUUUGAGACAGGGUCUCGCUCUGUCACCCAGGCUGGAGUGCAGUGAUACAAUCACAGCUCACUCCAACCUUGACCUCUUGGGUUCAGCAGUCCUCCUGCUUCAGGCUUCUGAGAAGUAGCCACCACACCUGGCUACUUUAAAAAAAUUAUUUGUAGAGGCAGGGUCUCCCUGUAUUGCCCAGGCGUCUUGAACUCCUGGUCUCAAGUGAUCCUCCCACCUCAGUCUCCCAAAGUGUUGGGAUUACAGGUGUGAACCACUGCACCUGGCCCAAAAUCUCUUGAUUGAUACAGUCCUCUUUAUUUUUCAAGAUCAAGUUAUGAUACCUUUACCAACAGUCAUACAUUCUUUUGGAACUUUGCACAAUAGUCAUAUGUUCUUUUAGAACUUUACACUUCUAUUCUUUAUUGCCCUGUAUUAUAAUUGCUUGUAUGCCUGACUCCUCUACAUGACUGUAUGGUUUGAACCAAAGUGUACGGGAUGUCGCACAGUGUCUAAUAGUGUCACACAACAAGUAAUAGGUAUUCAGUAAGUGAGUUAAGAUGAAAUAGUAACAUGAAAGAGUGCUUUGAAAGCAGUUUUUUAAAGAGUUUCUGUUCUGCUAAUUGUAAGCCAUUUUUUAAAUAAACAUGACGUGUGGUGUUGUCUUUAAAGUAAAAAUGGAAAAACCAGUGAGAUCAGACAUUGUUUUUUGCUUGCCCCUCAUUAUUACCUAGACAUUUUCAUUUAGAUAAAAACUAUGUCAGUCUCCUGGCUGUAGUCCUUUACGGAAGGAGCAAUAUUACAUUUAGCUCUGUUUCAUCUGGGAUUCAAUUGUGAAUUAUUCUUUAGAGAAAAAUUCUAUAAUAUGCUUCAUGAGACCUAUUCUUGUCUUCAGACUUGCCUAAAAUAUUUUUUGCUUGCUUAAGACCAGACAUGAGAAUUUUCUUGUAAGCAGAAAGCUUUGUGACAGGACUGGAUGAGUUUGUAGUGAAUGUUAGUGAUAGCUAUGACAGAAGUCUCAUAGCCUCAAUUGCAGAGUCAUAGUUCUGUCACAUGCUUCAACAAUAAUGUCUGAUAAGGGAGGAAGGAUGGGGAAGAAGAGUUACAAUUUACUAACUGUAUAUAUUUCAUCAUUUAUUGGCUUUGGUCAAAUAAAUUAAACAUUAACAUAGUAAUUUGUAGGGUUAAAAAAAUUUUUUUUUUCUAUUCGCGUUCUUGCUAUGUUCCCCAGGCUGGUUCCAAACUCCUGGGCUCAAGCGAUCCUCAAGCCUUCUGAGUAAUUGAGAUUGCCACACCCAGCUUUGCAGUGUUUGUUUUUUUUAAGAGACAGGAUACUCAUUCUGUGCCCAGGCUGGAGUGCAGUGGCCCUAUCAUAGCUCACCGCAGCCUCAAACUCAUAGGCUCAAGAGAUUGUCCUGCCUCAGCCACCUGAGUAGCUAGGGCAGCAGGCACACGCCAUCAUGCUCAGCUAAUUUGUAAACAUUUUUUUUUGUAGAGAUGGGGUCCUGCUGUGUUGUUGCCCAGGCUGGUCUUGAACUCCUGGCCUCAAGCAAUUCAUCCCAUCUUGGCUUCCCAAAGCACUGGAAUUAUAGGCAUGAGCCACAUCACCCAGCCUUGUAGUUAUUUUUAAAAUGAAGACAAGAGGAAUAGAGUAUACCUUUAAAAAUAUAUGAUACUGUGUAUUGGAUGAUUCUGAAAGGAUGUAUUUGCCUAUGAAGAAAAACCUUCUUGUUUUGAUGUCUGGUUGUUAGCUUUUUACUUUACUAAAGCCCAGUUAACUUUUCUGUGCUUUAGUUCCACAUCUGUAAAAUUACUCAUUUUAUAUUUCUCUAUCCACUUUGAAAAUUAAGUAAAUGCUCUUUGAAUUUCAACUUUUAAUUAUUUAAGCCAAGAUCUCUCUUCUGUAUUUUUUAUGUGUUCUUUAUUGUGGGCUUACUAAUUCUUGAAUUUAAAAAAAUCAUUUAAAUCAAGCAAUAGUAAUAGUAUAUGUUUAAGCAUAUAGUGUAUGUUUUUAAAUAAAUAAGCAGGCUGGGUUUUAGUGGCUCACCCCUAUAAUCCCAACACUUUAGGAGGCCAAGGCAAAAGGAUCACUUGAGUCCUGGAAUUGAAGACCAGUCUGGGCAACAUAGCGAGAUCACACCUCUACAAAAAAAAAAGUUUAAAAAUUAGCCAGGUAUGGUGGUAUGUACCUGUAGUUCUUAGCUAUUCGAGAGGCUGAGGUGGAAGGAUCGCUUGAGCCCAGAAAUUUGAGGUUAUGGUGAGUAGCGAUCACCCCACUGCACUCCAAGCCUGGUUGACAGAAUGAGACCCUGUCUCUAAAAUAAAAAUAAGCAAUAGCAUAUUUUUUUAAAAAACAACAAACAACUCUUUUAAGUCCAAAUUCCUUUUUGGAUCCUAUGGCUCAUAUCUUGCCACUGCCUGCUGCACUCUAUAUAGAAAUACUUUUAUUUCCUUCAGGAAUCCAGUUUUGUUCUCUCCGUGGGCCUUCUCAUAGUUAGUUCCCACUGCUGUUUGGAGCAUUAUUUUGGCAUUCUUCUCGCUCCUUCUAUUAUUUUCACCAAGAAAAGAGGAAAGCUCACACUUUCUAUUGUCAGUCUUGGAUAUCAUCCCAAAUGUCACUUUCUCAAGAAUCGUUUAAGAUAAACAGUUGUAUUAUCAGCCACAAAGAAGAUUAAAAAAAAAAAUUGCCCAAGAUCAUACAGUUUAGAAAUGGCAGAGUCAGAUCCAAACUUGGGCAGUUUUGCUCCAGAAGUCUUUAUCGCCACUGAUUUAUGCUUCCCCUACAUUGUAAUUGCCUGUUCAACAGUUUGCCCCACUAUGAGCACCUUUGGGGUAUUGUUUGCUUGUUUGUUUGUGACGGAGUCUUGCUCUGUAGCCCAGGCUGGAGUGCCAUGGCGCGAUCUCAGCUCACUGCAACCUCCACCUCCCGGGUUCAAGCGAUUCUCCUGCCUCAGCCUCCCGAGCAGCUGGGAUUACAGGCACGCACCACCACGUCCAGCUAAUUUUUGUAUUUUUAGUAGAGACGGGGUUUCACCAUGUUGGCCAGGCUGGUCUUGAACUCCUGACCUCAAGCGAUCCACCCGCCUAGGCCUCUGAAAGUGCUGGGAUUAUAGGUGUGAGCCACUGCCCCCCUUAAAAGAAGCACCUUUGGAGGAAAAAUUAUGCCUGUCUUGUUCAUUGUUAUAUCCCCAUGUGCUUAGCACAUACUAGGUGCUCAGAAAAUAUUUAAAUGAAUGAAAAUUCUUAUUUGAGGGAGAGAGUGUUUUGAUUAAAUUCUUCUCAGUACCUUUCAUGUAGUGUGUCAGUAAAUGCAGUAAUGUUUUCAUGCCUACUUAUUAUACAAAGUGAAAUUUUUAUGAUCAAGUUAAUCAUGGUUACAAGCUCAUUUUUUAUAACCUCUCUUAAUUCCUUUUUGCCCUAUACUGCGUAACGGUAUCACUUUGCAACUGUAAAAACUAGUGCUUUGUAGGCCUCUUUCUCAUAUUAUCCCUCUGUGAACUGUUAAAAUAUAGAUCAUUUUUAAUUAGUUUCUAAAGGGUAUGUAGGAAAUUGUAUAAAAUAAAAUUAUACUAGUAGAUGGACUCUGAUCAUUUAUACUGUUUAACCUUUUAACAAAUUACAGAGGUGUAAUUUCUCUGUGUGUAGAGGUUUUUUAAAGUAUCCCAUAUUUUAAACCUUGACUGUUACCUCAAAAAAAAAAGUGGUUUAUCUGUGUCCAGUAGUCACAUGGUGGAUAAUGAUGUAAGGCAUGCACAUUGUGUUCAUGUGUUUGUUGGAGAAGUUGGAAUGUCAUUAUACUUCAGUAGACUUUUCAAAUGAAAAAUCUGAAAGCUACUUCUAGCUGUAAUUCUGCUGUAAUUCUCAAUCAGGUCAGUAGACAGAGAACCAAAAAAGUCUUCCUCCUCUCUGAAUGUUCUUGCCAAAGCCUGACUUCUUUGAUUAAUCUUUCUUUUCUGUAUUCCUUACACUCUAUUACAGGGCUUCUCAACCUUGGCACUCUUGACAUUUGGGGCCAGGUAAUUCUUUGUUGUGGAGGACUGUCCUGUGCCUUGUGAAAUGUUUAGCAGCAUCCUUGGCUUCUACCUGUUAGAGGCAAAUAGUAUCCUUCCCCUUUCCCCUGUCCAGUUGUGGCAAUUUGAAAUGUCUCCAGACAUUGUCAAGUGUGGGGGUUAGGGAGGGUGGAAGGGGAGAACAAUCACCCCAGUUGAAAAUUGCAGCUUUCCUACAUCAUUCUGUCCACUUACUCAUUUGUUUUAAUAUCUUCCCCUCCCUCUCACACUUACCUUUUCAGACUUCCUGCCUCUCUGCUACUGCCUCAUUUCUCUGAACCUUUUUGCAGCCAUACUUCUAAAAAAGAAUUGUAAAACAUCUGUUCUCUCCAAGUUUUCACUUGCAGUUCAGUUUCCUCUUUUGAAUUCUAUUGAGACCACAUUUUUCUAGUUUUCCUCUAUCUCUCUGGCCGUUCCAUUUUUAUUUUCUUUAUCAGUUCUACCUAGUUGGACAAUGGCAUCAUCUUUGCCCCUUUCUUUCUUGUUCUCUGUUAUUCAACUCUCAAGUCUUCCUUUCUUGCCUCAUUUCCUAGUGCUUAAUGUUGUCUCUCAUAUGUGUUGUCCUAUUCAUUUUUAUUUUUUUUGGUAAGAACACAAUAUGAGAUCUACCCUUUCAACAAAUUUUUAAGUAUACAAUACAUUAUUGUUGACUAUAGGUACAGUGUUGUACAGUAGAUCUCUAGAGCUUACUCAUUUUGCUUAACUGAAACUGUAUGCCCGUUGAUUAAUAAGUCUGCAUUUCCCCCCAGCCCCUGACAACUCCCCUUUCACUCUUCGAUUCUAUGAAUUUGAUUAUUUUAGAUACUCACUUAUCAUUCUGGGUAAUGACCAGGCCUAGAUAAAGACCUCAUAUAAGUGGAAUUAUGUAGUAUUUGUCUUUCUGUGACUGGCUUAUUUUACUUAGCAUAAUGUCUUCAAGGUUCAUCCAUGUUGUCACCAUAUUUCCUUCUUCUCUGAGGCCAAAUAGUAUUCCAUUUAUGUAUUUACUACAUUUUCUUUAUUCAUUCAUCUGUCAAUGGAUAUUUAGGUUGUUUCCACAUCUUGGCUGUUGUGAUAUCUAUUAAUUGUUAAGCUGGUCUCUGUAUUGAAAUCUCCUUGCCUAUAUUUCUCCAUAGUUUAACAUCCUGCAAGGACCAGAGCAGAUUUUGUCUGUUGUUUUUUGGUUUUGGUUGUUGUUAUUGUUAGAGACAGUGUCUCAUUCUGUUGUCCAGGCUGUAGUGCAGUGGUGCAGUCAUGGCUCACUGCUCACUGUAACCUCAAAUGCCUGGACUCAAGUGAUCCCUCAUCUCAGCCUCCGGAGUAGCUGAGACUGCAGGCACACACUAUCACACUUGGCGAAUUUUUCUGUUUUUUUGUAACAGCCUGUUGCCCAGGCUGAUCUCAAACUCCUGGGCUGAAGCAAUCUGCCCACCUCGGCCUCCUGAAGUGCUGGGUUUACAGGCGUGAGCCCCCGCAUCUAGCUUGCACCUCAUUUAUUAAGGGUUCGUUAUGAGCCAGGCACUCUUUAAGGUCUUUGGACUAUAUAGUUACUGAAAUAAGACACAGUCCCAGUACUCCAAGAACUUAGUCUGUUUGAGGACAUGGAAAUUUUAAUUCAUUGCUCUUACAGAGUGAGUAUGGAAAUUGAAGUGUAUCCCAAACUUUCUGGUAGCAUAUAGGAAAGGGAUGAUUUCUCAGUUUGAUGUAAACCUCAUUCAAGUGCCACUUCUUACAUGCAGGCUAUCCUGGUCACUACCCAGUCUGAUUUGUGUUUUUAUACUCUCCUUUACUCAGUUCUCUUUCUUUUCCAGCCCCCAAAUCAUCAGCAUUUCCUAUGACUCAACACUUAGCUUUUCAUUCAUUCUUCUAGAUCCUUUUCUUUAGGAAAUGGAUUUAAUUUCAAGGGUUCAGCUGAAACUUUCAAAUUUGUAGUAGCUCCAACAAAACAUUUUAUUGUGAAGUAAUACACAUACAAAGUACAUUAAAUAAAUCUAACUUAAAAAAACAUUAUUUUAAAGCUGACAUCACUCUGGCCAUGAAAUAGAGCACUGUAAGUAUUCCAAAAGCCCCCCUCAUGCCUCUUCCCAAUCAUAACCACUUUCUUCCUCCUUUUAAAGGUUACUGCUAUUCUGAUCUUUAUGGUAAUUUCCUUGCAGAUUUUUAAAAAUAGCUUUAUUCUUGAUUACCAGCUGAAUAUUUAUCCCAAAACAAUAUAAUGUCAUUUUGGGAGGACAGUAGAGAAAGACAUUUUAUCAUAUCCCGUUUUGUGCCUGUAUUUUGAAUCCGCAAGAUCACCCCCAGGUUUGGUGAGGAGGAAGCACAGAACUCAACAUAUAGUAUGACUCAGCUAAGAGUUACUACAGCAAAAAAAAUACAAAGCGAAAAUGCCCAUGGGGCAACGUCCAGAGGAAACCAGGCACAAGCUUCAAGAGUCUUAUCCCAGUGAAGCCGCGUAGGAUGCAUUGACUUGUUACAAUCCUUGUGAAAUGUUGUCUUCCAGGGAAGCUUAUAAGAGACUCACUGCCCAGGGUGUUUAUUGGGGUAUAAUCACAUAGGCACCCUCUGUCUAGCUUGUACCAAAUUCCAAGCUCCCAGAAGGAAAGCAGAUAUUCAGCAUAAACCAUAUUGUUUGCACAAACAGUUUAGGCAUAGUAAAUCACCCUUAUUAAAUAGUCAGGGAAUUAUGGGAACACUCCCAAAAUCCAAUUUCCCAGAGACCUGCCAAGGGCCAUCUUUGCAUGCAGGCCUUUCUAAAGAUAGCAGUCUUAGGCCUGCUAUGUUGUCUUUUUGGCAUAGUACCUUUUGCUGUUUCUGAAUUCAAAAUUUAAAUAAGUAAAAAAUCAAUUAUCACUUUAUGUUAUGUUCUUUUUUUCUCCACCGUUGUUUUCUUUCCUAAUGUAUCAAGAUUAGCUGGGUGUGGUAGUGUGUGCCUCUGUAGUCUCAGCUACUUGGGAGGCUGAGUGCUGUAGUGCACAAUAAUUGCACUUAGGAUUAACCACUGCACUCCAGCCUGGGCGACAUACCAAACCCUGUUUCUCUUAAAAAAAAAAAAAAGUAUCAACAUUAGCUCAGUGCAAAGGUUGACUACUAUGAUAUGAUUGAAAGUAUAUUCCGGCCGGGCGCAGUGGCUCACGCCUAUAAUCCCAGCACUUUGGGAGGCUGAGGCAGGCAGAUCACUUAAGGUCAGGAGUUCGAGACCAGCCUGGCCAACAUAGUGAAGCCCCAUCUCUACUAAAAAUAAAAAAUUAGUUGGGUGUGGUGGCACAUGGCUGUAAUCUUAGCCGCUCGGGAGGCUGAGGCAGGGUAAUCGCUUGAACCCAAGAGGCAAAGGUUGCAAUGAGCUGAGAUCGUACCACUGCACUCUUUCUUAUGAAGGUUUCUGUGAUUAAGUUUGGAAAGGAUGAAUUAAACAAAGUUAAACAGAUUUCUUAACUACAGGACUCUUAGCCUUUUCACAGGAAUGUGCAUGACUUGGUGACUGCCUACAUGUCCUGCCUCAUCUCACGUUUUUUUUCCCUGACCCACUUUGCUUACUCUGCCCAGAUUUAAUCUAGUACUAAGGAUCAAAUUACAAUUGUCUAUGUUACAUGGGCAUUUUCUCAGUUUGCCACAGCAAUAUUAUGAUCACUUUACCAUCUUGAAUAUGAACUGUCCCUCCAUCUCUGCUCAAUUACUGUGUCAGAGCAAGCAAACGUUUUUACUAUUUCAUUCAUAGAUUCAGCAAAAUUUGUUAAGCACCUACUAUAUUUGCCAGACACAGUUCUAGGCACUGGAGAUACAACAGUGAAUAAAAGAAAAACCCUGACCUUAUAUAGUUUACCUUAUAGUGGGGAGUGGAAAAAGGGAACAAUAAUUAAAAAUACAUGUUAUGCCCAGUAUGGUGGCUCACACCUGUAAUCCUUAAACUCUGAGAGGCCAAAGUGGGAGGAUCACUUGAGGCCAAGAGUUCAAGACCAACCUUUAUAACACACCAAGACCUCAACAGAAAAAAUAAAAAUAAAUUAGCUGGGCACAGUGGUGCAUACUGUAGUCCCAGUUAUUCGGGAGGAUCACUUGAGCCCAGGAGUUUGAAGCUACAGUGAGCUAUGAUUGUGCCACCACACUUCAGCCUGAGUGACAGAGUGAGACUGUCUCUAUUUUUUAAAAAAAAUUAAAAAAAAAAAGACUGGGCAUGGUGGCUUGCACCUGUAAUCCUAGCACUUUGGGGAGGCCAAGGUGGGUAGAUCACCUGAAGUCAUGAGUUCGAGACCAGCCUGGCCAACAUGGUGAAACCCUAUCUCUACUAAAAAUACAAAAAAAUUAGCUGGGCAUGGUGGCAGAUGCCUGUAAUCCCAGCUACUCGGGAGGCUGAGGCAGGAGAAUUGCUUGAACCCGGGAGGCAGAGGUUGCAGUGAGCCGAGAUCACACCAUUGUACUCCAUCCUGGGCAACAAGAGCAAAACUCCAUCUCAAAAAAAAAAAAAAAAAGAUACAUUUUGCUCCUAGGCAUAUACUUAAGAGAAGUGGAAGUACAUGUCUACACAACUUGUACAAAUGUUUGUAACAGCAUUAUUCAUAAUAACCAAAAAGUGGAAACAACCCAAAUGUCCAUCAAUGGAUGGAUGGAUGAAUGAAUAAAUCAAAUACAAUGUGGUAUAUCCAUACAAUGAAAUAUUAUACAGCAAAUAAAGAGGAAUAAAGUAGUACUGAUAAAUGCUACAAUGUGGAUGGACCUUGAAAACAUCAUGCUAAAGUGAAAGAAGCCAGUCACAAAAGCCCACAUUAUUAUAUGAUCCCAUUUAUAUAAAAUGUCCAAAAUAAUAGAGGUAGAAAUUAGAUUAGUAGUUGCCUAGGAUUGGGGAAUUGAGGUGAGUGACUGCUAAUGGAACUUCUUUUAGGGGGUGAUGAAAAUGUUCUACAUGUCAGAACCACUGAUGGCUGCACAGAUGUAUCUACAAGUAAUAUAGUGUCAGUUAAGCACAACGUUCUCAAGAAAUUCAGUAAAAAGUCAAGCCUAACAUUGUACACCUCAAUGGCUAACAAAAGCAUCCUCCAGUUAUUUGGAAAAUUUAUCCAUCUCGCUUCCUAGCAACAGCAGAAAUGGAUGAAAAGAGGCUGCUGGAUCCAGGGUUGAAGGUUCAUAAAGGCCUCUGGGAUUAUACUCUGAAGAACCCGCAGACGGAAUGCCUGAGUGACUGAAGAAAAUGGGUGCUAAUGCAUCUAAUUAUCCUCAUUCAUGUUCCCCGAGGGUAGGGGGAAAUUCACAGGCCCAACAGACUUUUAUAGGGACCUCAUCCUAUUCUCAGCAAGGCUAUGGUUGCGAAUCAAAGUUGUAUAGCCUUGACCAUGGCCAUGAGAAACCACAAGACAAAAAAAAGAGAACCUCUGGUCUUGCCACCCUCAAAAAGAAGUUUAUUAAGCGUCGGAAAUCUAAUAGGUCUGCCGAUCAUGCCAAGCAGAUGCGAGAACUCCUCUCUGGGUGGGAUGUUAGAGAUGUCAAUGCAUUAGUGGAGGAAUAUGAGGGAACAUCAGCAUUAAAGGAGCUUUCUCUACAAGCCAGUUUGGCUAGACCAGAAGCCCGGACAUUGCAGAAAGAUAUGGCUGAUCUUUAUGAGUACAAGUAUUGUACUGAUGUAGACUUAAUAUUUCAAGAAACUUGUUUUCCUGUUCAUCGUGCCAUUUUGGCAGCAAGGUGUCCAUUUUUUAAAACACUGCUUUCUUCCUCACCAGAGUAUGGGGCAGAGAUAAUAAUGGACAUCAAUACAGCUGGUAUUGAUAUGCCCAUGUUUUCUGCUUUGUUACACUACCUUUAUACAGGAGAGUUUGGAAUGGAGGACUCAAGGUUUCAAAAUGUCGAUAUCCUUGUUCAGCUUAGUGAAGAAUUUGGAACACCAAAUUCCCUUGAUGUAGAUAUGCGUGGACUCUUUGAUUACAUGUGUUAUUAUGAUGUCGUCCUUAGUUUUUCUUCAGACUCUGAACUGGUUGAAGCUUUUGGUGGAAAUCAGAACUGUUUAGAUGAAGAGCUCAAAGCCCACAAGGCUGUUAUUUCUGCACGGUCCCCAUUUUUUCGAAAUUUAUUACAAAGGAGGAUACGAACUGGUGAAGAAAUCACAGACCGAACUUUGAGGACUCCCACAAGAAUUAUAUUAGAUGAGUCCAUUAUACCAAAAAAAUAUGCAACAGUGAUAUUACACUGUAUGUAUACCGACGUGGUGGACCUCUCUGUUUUGCACUGUAGCCCCUCUGUGGGGAGUCUCAGUGAAGUUCAGGCUCUCGUCGCAGGGAAGCCAAACAUGACCAGGGCAGAAGAAGCCAUGGAACUUUACCACAUAGCACUGUUCUUGGAAUUUAACAUGCUUGCACAAGGCUGUGAGGAUAUCAUUGCUGAGAGCAUCUCAUUAGAUACCUUAAUUGCCAUCCUCAAGUGGAGUUCUCAUCCAUAUGGCUCUAAAUGGGUGCACCGACAAGCUUUACAUUUCCUCUGUGAGGAAUUUUCCCAGGUCAUGACUUCGGAUGUUUUUUAUGAACUCAGCAAAGACCAUCUGCUUACUGCUAUCCAGUCUGACUACCUACAGGCAAGUGAACAAGAUAUCCUUAAAUAUCUGAUUAAAUGGGGAGAGCAUCAGUUGAUGAAAAGAAUAGCAGAUAGAGAGCCAAACUUACUGAGUGGCACUGCCCAUAGUGUGAACAAAAGAGGUGUAAAAAGACGGGACCUGGACAUGGAAGAGCUCAGAGAGAUCCUUUCUUCUCUCUUACCUUUUGUGCGAAUUGAACACAUCUUACCUAUAAACAGUGAAGUCUUAAGUGAUGCAAUGAAAAGAGGCUUGAUUAGUACUCCUCCAUCAGAUAUGCUUCCUACAACAGAAGGUGGGAAGUCAAAUGCCUGGUUACGGCAAAAAAAUGCUGGCAUCUAUGUUCGUCCUCGACUCUUCUCUCCCUAUGUGGAAGAAGCAAAGUCAGUGCUAGAUGAGAUGAUGGUGGAACAAACGGAUCUUGUGCGCUUGCGAAUGGUUAGAAUGUCCAAUGUGCCAGACACGCUCUACAUGGUCAAUAAUGCCGUGCCACAGUGUUGUCACAUGAUCAGCCACCAGCAGAUCAGCAGCAACCAGUCAAGCCCUCCUUCAGUUGUAGCCAACGAAAUUCCAGUUCCUCGUCUCCUCAUUAUGAAAGACAUGGUCAGACGACUGCAGGAACUGCGGCACACGGAGCAGGUGCAGAGGGCCUAUGCCCUGAACUGCGGGGAAGGCGCCACUGUCAGCUAUGAAAUUCAGAUUCGAGUGCUAAGAGAGUUUGGUCUUGCAGAUGCUGCUGCAGAGCUGUUGCAGAAUCCUCACAAAUUCUUUCCUGAUGAACGUUUUGGGGAUGAAAGUCCACUCUUGACAAUGAGACAGCCUGGGAGAUGUCGCGUAAACAGUACACCUCCUGCAGAAACCAUGUUUACAGAUCUGGACUCUUUUGUGGCCUUCCAUCCACCCUUGCCCCCUCCACCACCUCCCUACCACCCCCCAGCUACCCCAAUCCAUAACCAACUCAAAGCAGGCUGGAAGCAAAGACCUCCCAGUCAGCACCCUUCACGUUCAUUUUCUUAUCCCUGUAAUCAUUCGCUGUUCCACUCCAGAACAGCUCCUAAAGCUGGCCCUCCCCCAGUCUACUUGCCGAGUGUGAAAGCUGCACCGCCUGAUUGUACCAGCACUGCAGGACUGGGCAGACAGACGGUGGCUGCUGCUGCCGCCACCACCACCUCAACAGCAACAGCAGCAGCAGCAGCAGCAUCUGAGAAGCAAGUGCGAACACAACCUGUGCUGAAUGAUCUGAUGCCAGACAUCGCGGUGGGUGUGUCCACACUGUCACUCAAGGACAGGAGGCUUCCAGAGCUUGCUGUAGACACAGAAUUAAGCCAGUCAGUUUCUGAAGCAGGACCAGGGCCUCCCCAGCAUCUGUCGUGUAUUCCACAGAGACAUACACACACUUCUCGGAAAAAACACACACUAGAGCAAAAAACAGACACCAGAGAAAAUCCACAGGAAUAUCCGGAUUUCUAUGACUUCUCAAAUGCUGCUUGCAGACCUUCUACUCCUGCUCUCAGCAGACGCACCCCUUCCCCUUCGCAAGGUGGAUAUUUUGGUCCCGAUCUGUACAGCCACAAUAAGGCAUCACCAAGUGGCUUAAAGUCAGCCUACCUACCUGGUCAGACGUCUCCUAAAAAACAGGAAGAAGCUAGGAGAGAAUAUCCACUUUCCCCUGACGGGCAUCUACACAGACAAAAGAAUGAGCCGAUACACCUGGAUGUCGUUGAGCAACCUCCCCAGCGGUCAGACUUUCCUUUGGCAGCCCCAGAAAAUGCUAGUACCGGUCCAGCCCAUGUCAGGGGACGAACUGCAGUAGAAACUGACUUGACUUUUGGGCUGACUCCUAACAGACCUUCACUUUCUGCAUGUAGCUCUGAAGCUCCCGAAGAGAGAUCCGGUAGAAGACUGGCAGACAGUGAGUCCCUGGGCCAUGGAGCUCAGAGAAAUACAGAUUUGGAAAGGGAAGAUUCAAUAAGCAGAGGAAGGAGGUCACCAAGCAAGCCGGACUUCCUCUACAAAAAGUCUGCCCUCUGAGAGCAACCUCCAAGUCGUCUGUGCCUGAGAUGUGAAACAUCCCAUUUUAUGAUGUAACCCAACAACUUACAGACCAGUUCAUCAAUGCCAGCUGAUAACUCGGUUUCACAUGAUUUUGUUCUAGUUUUUGUGUAUAUAUGUGUUUAUUAGACAUGGCAUGCUAAGAAGGUUUUGUUUUUUUUUUUUAAUGUUGCAUCUGUCUAAUUUGUCUUUGAACAAUUAUGUCGGGAGGCAUUUUUAAGAACAAGCAGGCUGGCACUUUUUAUUUCUCUUUACAAAUGAUGGAAUUUUUUUGCACUUGUACAUUUAUUUUCUCUGUAUUGAUUUUAUAUCAGUAUGUUAAACUUUAUUGCCACAUUUAAAGGACUGUAUUUUCAUACUUUUUUGCAUUUUACCUUUCAUCUACCAAUCCAUGUGCAUUGGAUUGCACACUAAGAUGUAUUUUCUUACGAAAUAGUUCUGUGUUUAUUUUUUAAUUAUAGAAAUUCCAAAGAACAGCACAUCAGAAUGCUCCUCUCUUUUCAGUAAUUGUUUUAGUUCAGAGAUCUUCCCGCUCAGCCUCCAUAAAUCUAAUGUCAUUUUUUUUUUAAUAAGUCCUAGGAGCUGGGCUUCAUUCCUCCAGCGGGAGUCCAGUCAGGGUCCUGAAGUUUGCUGGUUCAGGAAAGAACAGGAAAGAGAAAAGCCUUCUGUGCCCAGGCUAAAGCUGUUACAUUUCCACAGUGUGGAUGCAGUCAGAAUCCCUGCACAUUCUGGUCAUAAGGAUUAGAGUCACCAGAUGAGGCUCUAAACAGAUCGCAUCCCUUGGAAUUAGAAAGCAGUGGAGACCGGGCGCAGUGACUCACACCUGUGAUCGGCACUUCGGAAGGCCGAGGCGGGCAGAUCACUGAAGCUCAGGAGUUCAAGACCAGCCUGGGCAACAUGGCGAAACUCCAUUUCUAUAAAAAAUACAAAAAAAAAAAAAUCUAGCCAGGCGUGGUGGUGCGUGCCUGUAGUCCCAGCUACUUGGGGGGCUGAGGUGGCAGGAUCGCUUGAGCCUGGGAGGUUGAGACUGCAGUGAGCCAAGAUUGCACCACUGUGCUCCCACCUGGGCAACAGUGAGACCCUGUCUCAAAAAAAAAAAAAAAGGCAGUGGAAAUAGAGAAGUAACUUAAAGGUCACACUGACAGAAUUUCUGGUUCUGAGCGUCAACUCUCCAGCUGUGAUGGCGGAACUGACUGCUUGCUGCCUUUAAUUGUCUUGCUCUCUAUGGGAAAAAAACAAAAGGGCUUCAGUCUCAUGGAUGUUAUUUGGUGUUUGUAAAGAUACGUUUUCUUUUAAACGAUUUUCAAAAUAUGUCUAAAUUUUGGUGUUGUGUAAUGCAUAAUGCUUUCUCACCAACAGAAAAAAGGAAAAAAAUUGUUUUCAGUUAAACACUACAUGUCCUACUUGAACUCCACUGGGACGCUGGUUUGGCAUUUACUAAACCACUGAGCACAUGGGGUCUUUCAGGAUCCUCUCCCUUGGAAGGGCAAUGUGUGAGCUAAGGACUGUUUUUUUUCUUACUCUCCAAUGUAAAUAUAUGAGUAUUUGAGUUUUUAAAUCACUUCAACAUUAUUUGAGCAUUUACUUUGUAUUUUUACAAACACAUAAACACACAGCCGUAGCACUUAGAAGAAAAGAGGCUUUCUAAGCAUUCCUUCCUCUGCAGGAUAUUUGGGAUCCUCUUUUCUAUGUAUGUAUAUAUAUAAAAAACUAUGAAUCACUCACACUCACUCGAAAACUAUGCAGGGCUAGGGAGCGUUUAUGAGCUACCGGGUAAAUGAAUUACAUGCACUUUGAAGUAAAUAGGUUUUCUAUUGGGUGUCAACAACGCUGAUUUCUCCCAAAACUAUAGUUUCUCUUACGGUCUUUUCCUCCUUUACCCUGUGGAUAUACACUCAGGAAUAAUCUGACAUUUUAGAAAAGCCGAACAGUAGAUAGUCUCCAAGAUGGGAAACAUGUCGUGUGUCUGCACGCCCCGGCAAACUGCCGCCACUCGUUCUGCUGCCUGACUGGUUAGCUGCUGUGCGGGUGCGCUCGGUGACACUGGUGGUGGUGCACGCUCCCGAGCUCCCAGAGUUAACACUAAUCUGCAGGUCGGCUGUGCAUCGCAUUCGAGGCUCCUUUUUUAAAGAGAAAAGCAUAGGCCUCUGUUCUCAUUUGUAAGAAGUUUGACUCAUAAUAGAAGACGGUGUCUUUUGAAGCCCAGUCUCUGUCUGUCUUCAGAAACAAAAGUGAAUGCCGUCAUGUUCCUUGAUGUGUGUUUCUGCCACAUAUGUAUGUUGACAUGUUCAUGUACUGCGCCGGUACUGCAAGUAAGACUCAACAGACCUAAUUUGGAUGGGGAGAAAAACUCUCAUCCCUGACCCUUCCCCCCCCGCAAAUGUUAGACCAGAGCUGUUGAUCCCACACAUUCAUUUUUCUGAAAAUUCAUGAACUAUUCUCUCAUAUCCCUGAAAUAUAAAAGUAAGUGGCCACUAUUCCUAAGAUUAUUUAGUUUAUAAAGUUUGCUUUUAAUCAUACAAUAGCUUACCUGGCUAAAACUUUGCGUAUAAAGGGAAAACUUGCUUUAAUCUGUGGGAUUGCGGACCGAUGCGACUUGCAGAAGGUAAACAGGCGUGGGUUUUGUGUGCGUUAGGUUAGGUGUUAGUGGACUUUUAAUGUAUCUUGUGAAGUAUGGUUACUAGGGUAGGUUCAAGAGCUACAUGCCUCUGGCUUUUGAACCCAUCUAUUAAAUCUUUUUUAAUGCUGUACUAAGAUAAAUGUGAAGUCUGAGUAAGGUUGCUCUCAGAAAAAAAAAAAAAGCAUAUAUAUAUAUAAAAUAAAAUUUAGGCCAUGGGAACUGGCAUUUUACUUGGUAUAGGAAUUUAAUGAGAACCAAAUCACAAAAAUACCAGAUCUCCUUUUGAGAUCGUGGACAAUCAGGCCUUUGGACAAUCACCGCUUCCAGUGCCCGCUGUGCGUUGAGGUUAGAGACCUACCGUUUACACGCUAGAGCCGAGAGGACGUUCAAGUUUCUUAAAGAUGCUGUUGGUCUUUUUUCUUAUGUUAUUGUUUUAGUUUUGUGAUUUUGAUGAAUAAUUGAAGUUCAGAGUCACCCGUGGCUCCUAAGGAAAAAACAGCAUCAUGAAAGGCAAAAAGUAUUUGAAACGUAAUUGUUUCAAUUUUCCACGCCCGUUCUCACAUGCCCCCUUUAGCUUUAUUUCUGGGAACAUGUCACUAGACCUCAGCUAGCCUGACACCGCAAUAACCCGUUAGGCUUUGAGGCUUUUCAGUGAAUUCUUGACAUUUAAAUCUUCUUAUAGAAUUCUUUAUGAAGCCUUAACUAAUUCUUGUUUUUGCUUCCUCAGAAACUUUUUAUUGCAUCUGCCAUCCUUCAUUGGAUUUUUGUUUUGGUUUGUUGUUGCCAUUCUAGCAAUGAGCUUAGUCCUUGUACAUCUGCAUUAAGGUGCCGAUGCAGAAGGCAAAUUGGAAACACGCGCCAGCGGCAGUGGGGCUCAAAGCCGACCUCCAUGCAUCAUUCUCUAGAGUUGAAAGGAUUGACAUUUCUCAGUAACUACCCGGCAAAAUAUAUAUUUUCAUAAUGUUGAAUUUGCCUUUUAGGAAAACAAUGUUUCAUGAAACACUUGUAAGAUACUUAUUUUGAAAUUAAUUAUAAGGCAUUCAUAUUUUUAGGACUGAAUUCAAAGGGAAAUGCUUCUUUGACUUUUUUUCAUUGUUCGGUUGACUUUCAGCUUUCUGGAGUGACAAAGCAGCAGUGAUGGGUGCUAUUCCUGGUUCUGUGGUGGUUUACUUUGUCUACUAAGUGAUUUACUUUCAAACCUCAUUACAGAUAAUCUUACUAAAAGACUUAACAUGCACACUGCUAAAAGGUGUUUUACUGUUUUCCAUUAACGCUGUUGUAUGAACAAUAUUUGGUGACAUGUUGUCUUUUUGUCCUGUAGAUUGUCAUAUCUGUUAUGUAGUUAUCCUUUUGGCAAGUCCUUUGAUUUUUUUUUCCUCUAGAAAAUCCUCAGACUGUCAAUCUUCCAUAUUUUGAAUAUUAUAAUGCUGUGGCCAUUUCUAUAGAAAGAUUACUUGCAAGUGUGUGUCUUGAAAAUAACCUCUUGUAUUUGUGUGUUUAUGUGAGUUCUGUCUAAGAGAUCAGAUAAGCUCUGGAAGCUUCAUCAUCUGUACCUACAUGUAACUGUAUCUGGGUUACAUGGGCAGGCGGUACCAAGUCCUGCUCUUCGAUGGGGUGGCUGAGAGAUAAAGGUUCCUGAACUCUCCUUGCUGUGUAUGCACCACAUCUGUACUUCAGAGAGGUGGAAAAUCAUCUACAACACUGCGUUUCUUGUGGUUGUGCUGUUACUGGUAUAAAGUCAAGUGCCUUCAAUGCUAAAGGCUCAGAAAUUUUUCUUAAACUGAUUUCAUGUCCUAUGCAAGUGUUUUCUACAACCUGCAUAACCAGUACUUUGUAAAACUUGUUUACGCUUCAAUUGUACAUAGUGAUUUUUAAAGAAAUAUAUAGUAUUUUUAUUUAGGUACCUCCAAACUUGAAUUCGUCUGUGUGAAGCAUUGUAAAACGAUACAUUUCUCUUUUGAGUACCAUUACAGUUGUACAGAGGUUUUCACUGCUUCUAUUUUUCUACUGUUACUGAUAAGCAUGUAACACUGACUUUAUCCUACAUAUAGUUGGCAUUUCAAAUAAAUGGCUUGUAUAGAA